AGAGCUGGAACGCUCGGCUAUCGGACUGGGUGGCACCGGGCGCAGGCCGCUGCCCUUGAAGCGCCGGCCUUGGCUGGAGCCCGUGGACCAGCGCCCACCCGGACGCCGGGGCGGGAGCGGGCGGUUCCAUCGACCCUGAGGGUGGACCAAGGAGACUGAGGGUUCCACCCGUGGCAUCACAAUUACCUCCGCGGCGGCGAGGCCAGAGAGGCAUUUCCAAGGAGACGCGGGCGCACUGCCCCUCCCUUGCUUCCUCCUCUUCCCUCCUUCCUCUCCUAGUUUCUUCCCUCCCUUCCCGCCCUACUCCUUCCCUCCCUUCCCACCCUACUCCUUUCGGCUGCUCUGGUGCCCACCCCCAGUGCCUCGAGGUCGAGGAGAGCUCCUCGGCCCCGCAGGACGGGGAGGAUUCUGUACAGAUGAGCAUAACUUGUGGCUGGAAGAGAAGAAAGAAGUGAAGACACUGAGCUCACUGAAGUACUUGCCGUGCUGUGGAAAACAGGAGGAGGAGCUGACCAGAGACUUAUAGGAGGAUGACCAAGUGCCACUGAAGGCUUGCUGAAGACCCCAAGCAAUCAGUUUCCCUUCCUUAAGCAGACCUCAAGUCCAGUGCCUCAAGGGAUAAAGCUAGUUGUGGGAAGGAAAGGCAAAGGGGCAGACUGUCUUGUGGCUGCUAAUGGCUGAGGGAGCUGCCACCCCAGUUGGAGGUCUGCUUAGGGUCAUCCUCUGUCCAGGCUCCACACACCCUGGGACAGUUUCUGGAGCUGUCCCUCCUUGCCUAGACCCUGGCUGGCUCCUAUUCAUCACUAACUCUAGUGAUGCUCCUUCCAAGAAGUCUUCCAUAGUCCCCAGUCCUCCUUUCCAGUCCUGAUGUAAACAGGUUACCCAGCUGGGAGAGAGGACAUCUGCUGGCUGGUGUGGCGUCCAGCACUGAUGUGUCUACCUUCUCUGAAGCUUUGAAUUGGUGCUGCCAGCCCAGUCCCAGCUCUGCACACCUUGCUCUGCUCUAAGAGAAAUGGGGAGGAGGUCUGUUGGCCUGAGGCAGGCCCAGCGGAAGCCCACUGUCCCUCAGGCUUCUGGCUCUGGGUCCCUGGGGGAGUGAUGGGAGCCAGGCUGAGAGUCCCAUGUGUGGCAGGCUGAAGGACUCUUCAGAGGAUAGCAGCAGCUCCCGGGGCGCGGGCCCAACCUGCUCCCAUGUCAUCGAGUCCCCUUGCUUUGAGCUCACACCGGAGGAGGAGCAUGUGGAGCGAUUCCGGUAUGGCUGGUGCAAAAGCUACAGACCUGUCUCUGUGGCAGUGAUCCACCAUCCACUCUACCAUGAGUGUGGGGCAGAUGAUCUAAAUGAAGAAGAGGAAGAGGAGGAGGAGGAAAGCAAGCCCCCCAUCCCGACACAGGUGGGGCCCGCCACCGCCUCCCCUGACCUAGGCACCAGCAUGGCCACUGGUACCCCUGACUCCACAGCGCCCAUCACCAUCUGGCGCUCUGAGAGCCCCACAGGGAAGGGUCAGGGCAGCAAGGUGAUCAAGAAGGUAAAGAAGAAAAAGGAAAAAGAGAAAGACAAGGAGGAGAUGGAUGAGAAGGCAAAGCUGAAGAAAAAAGCCAAGAAAGGCCAGUUGACUAAGAAGAAAAGCCCGGUUAAAUUGGAGCCUUCCCCGCCAGACGUGAGCCGAUCAUUAAGCGCAAGACAGCUGGCCAGGAUGUCCGAGUCCAGCCCAGAAAGCCGGGAAGAGCUGGAGAGCGAGGACAGUUACAAUGGCCGGGGGCAGGGAGAACUGUCCAGCGAGGAUAUUGUGGAAUCAUCAUCGCCCAGGAAGAGAGAGAACACAGUCCAGGCCAAAAAGACAGGGGCAAAGCCCUCACAAGCCAGGAAGGUAAACAAGAGAAAAUCUCCCCCAGGAUCAAACCCCAACCUCAGUUGAGGCCAGGGUGGUCAGGGUGCAGAAUAAAUGCCAUCGAGCCUGUGGCUGGCCCUCUGCUGCUGUUCUCUCCCUCCAACCUGGCUGUUUCUUGCGGGGCAAGGGGUGGGCUCAGGGCUGCAGGGGUUUCUCAAAGGCAAUCCAGCUUUCACAAAGGAAGCCCAUGGGAAGGCAGGUGGGAGGGAAAGGAAGGGGCACAGCCCUAUUUCUUCCUACCUGCUAGGACAAGGUGGAAGAGUGUAUCUGGGGUGGGAAGGAGGGCUUCCCCUCUCUGCUGCGAGAGACUGGUCUGUGUGAAAUCCACUUCUGGGACAGGCAGUACUGUCUGCAGCGAUACCCCCAAUAAACGGAACUUUUUAACCCA